GGAAGUGCCGAAUGGGGACCAAGAUGGCGGACCUUGAUUCGCCUCCGAAGCUGUCAGGGGUGCAGCAGCCGUCUGAGGGGGUGGGAGGUGGCCGCUGCUCCGAAAUCUCCGCUGAGCUCAUUCGCUCCCUGACAGAGCUGCAGGAGCUGGAGGCUGUAUACGAACGGCUCUGCGGCGAGGAGAAAGUGGUGGAGAGAGAGCUGGAUGCUCUUUUGGAACAGCAAAACACCAUUGAAAGUAAGAUGGUCACUCUCCACCGAAUGGGUCCUAAUCUGCAGCUGAUUGAGGGAGAUGCAAAGCAGCUGGCUGGAAUGAUCACCUUUACCUGCAACCUGGCUGAGAAUGUGUCCAGCAAAGUUCGUCAGCUUGACCUGGCCAAGAAACACUCAACAAAUUUGGAAUAGAGGGGAACUUCUCAGCCUGAUAAAGAGCAUCUGUGAAAAACCACAGCUGGCCAGGUGUGGUGGCUCAUGCCUGCAAUCCUAACACUUUGGGAGACCAAAGCAGUAGGAUCUCUUGAGGCCAGAAGUUGGAGACCAAACCUUGGAACACAAACCGCCUCUAUCAGGCCAUUCAGAGAGCUGAUGACAUCUUGGACCUGAAGUUCUGCAUGGAUGGAGUUCAGACUGCUUUGAGGAGUGAAGAUUAUGAGCAGGCUGCAGCACAUACUCAUCGCUACUUGUGCCUGGACAAGUCGGUCAUUGAGCUCAGCCGACAGGGCAAAGAGGGGAGCAUGAUUGAUGCCAACCUGAAAUUGCUGCAGGAAGCUGAGCAACGUCUCAAAGCCAUUGUGGCAGAGAAGUUUGCCAUUGCCACCAAGGAAGGUGAUCUGCCCCAGGUGGAGCGCUUCUUCAAGAUCUUCCCACUGCUGGGUUUGCAUGAGGAGGGAUUAAGAAAGUUCUCGGAGUACCUUUGCAAGCAGGUGGCCAGUAAAGCUGAGGAGAAUCUGCUCAUGGUGCUGGGGACAGACAUGAGUGAUCGGAGAGCUGCAGUCAUCUUUGCAGAUACACUUACUCUUCUGUUUGAAGGGAUUGCCCGCAUUGUGGAGACCCACCAGCCAAUAGUGGAGACCUAUUAUGGGCCAGGGAGACUCUAUACCCUGAUCAAAUAUCUGCAGGUGGAAUGUGACAGACAGGUGGAGAAGGUGGUAGACAAGUUCAUCAAGCAAAGGGACUACCACCAGCAGUUCCGGCAUGUUCAGAACAACCUGAUGAGAAAUUCUACAACAGAAAAAAUCGAACCAAGAGAACUGGACCCCAUCCUGACUGAGGUCACCCUGAUGAAUGCCCGCAGUGAGCUAUACUUACGCUUCCUCAAGAAGAGGAUUAGCUCUGAUUUUGAGGUGGGAGACUCCAUGGCCUCAGAGGAAGUAAAGCAAGAGCACCAGAAGUGUCUGGACAAACUCCUCAAUAACUGCCUUUUGAGCUGUACCAUGCAGGAGCUAAUUGGCUUAUAUGUUACCAUGGAGGAGUACUUCAUGAGGGAGACUGUCAAUAAGGCUGUGGCUCUGGACACCUAUGAGAAGGGCCAGCUGACAUCCAGCAUGGUGGAUGAUGUCUUCUACAUUGUUAAGAAGUGCAUUGGGCGGGCUCUGUCCAGCUCCAGCAUUGACUGUCUCUGUGCCAUGAUCAACCUCGCCACCACAGAGCUGGAGUCUGACUUCAGGGAUGUUCUGUGUAAUAAGCUGCGGAUGGGCUUUCCUGCCACCACCUUCCAGGACAUCCAGCGCGGGGUGACAAGUGCCGUGAACAUCAUGCACAGCAGCCUCCAGCAAGGCAAAUUUGACACAAAAGGCAUCGAGAGUACUGACGAGGCGAAGAUGUCCUUCCUGGUGACUCUGAACAACGUGGAAGUCUGCAGUGAAAACAUCUCCACUCUGAAGAAGACACUGGAGAGUGACUGCACCAAGCUCUUCAGCCAGGGCAUUGGAGGGGAGCAGGCCCAGGCCAAGUUUGACAGCUGCCUUUCUGACUUGGCCGCCGUGUCCAACAAAUUCCGAGACCUCUUGCAGGAAGGGCUGACGGAGCUCAACAGCACAGCCAUCAAGCCACAGGUGCAGCCUUGGAUCAACAGCUUUUUCUCCGUCUCCCACAACAUCGAGGAGGAAGAAUUCAAUGACUAUGAGGCCAACGACCCUUGGGUACAACAGUUCAUCCUUAACCUGGAGCAGCAAAUGGCAGAGUUCAAGGCCAGCCUGUCCCCGGUCAUCUACGACAGCCUAACCGGCCUCAUGACUAGCCUUGUUGCCGUCGAGUUGGAGAAAGUGGUGCUGAAAUCCACCUUUAACCGGCUGGGUGGUCUGCAGUUUGACAAGGAGCUGAGGUCGCUCAUUGCCUACCUUACCACGGUGACCACCUGGACCAUCCGAGACAAGUUUGCCCGGCUCUCCCAGAUGGCCACCAUCCUCAAUCUGGAGCGGGUGACCGAGAUCCUCGAUUACUGGGGACCCAAUUCCGGCCCAUUGACGUGGCGCCUCACCCCUGCUGAAGUGCGCCAGGUGCUGGCCCUGCGGAUAGACUUCCGCAGUGAAGAUAUCAAGAGGCUGCGCCUGUAGCUGCCUGGAUGAGCACACCUGGCUCAUCACACUUGCAGGCCUGUUCCCUAAGGGGCCCCAGCCAAGGAGCUGAGCGAGGCUGUCUGGCUUGGGGGAGAUCUGACAGCCCAGACCUUUCUACGGCUGGCAGCAGAGAAACAAAGUCUGGACCCACUCCAUGCUCUGCCCUCAGACCUGGCCAGGUGAUGCUCUGGGGGCAGCAUCUCCCCACCGAGAGAAGCGGGCUCCUAAUGAGGUGGGAAAGCCACGGCAGGCAGCGAGCAGCCCAGGCCAGCUUUCUGCAUGGAUGGUCAGUCUCUUGCCCUCAAACACUACAGCAAACAAGCUACCCCUGCCAGUCCUAGACAACUUGGGUACAUCUGGGGACCUAGCAGUUAGGCUUGACUUUGAGGAGAGGCUGUGAUGUUUAUGAUCCCUGAAUAAAGCUACUCCUUGGAGAGAUG